CACUCCCCGCGGCGCGAGCGGCUGACUGCCCGUAGAGGAAACGACAUUCGGAGCUGCGCUCCCGCCCACGCCGGCCCUGACGCGGGCCUCGUCAGCCAGUAACAGGGAGCAGAGGUGGGAGUUAGCGAGGCGACCACGAAAACGGUGAAGGUCGGAACCGACAGCCUCCUCCGAGAAGGGCAGGAGCUGGGAGGAGGCGGCAGCGGCGGCGGCAGAAACAGCAGCGGCGGCGGCGGCGGCAGCUGGGAGGAGGUGGUGACGGUGGCAACGGCAGCGUCGGGGACGAUGGCGCGACUCGUGGCAGUGUGCAGGGACGGGGAGGAGGAGUUCCCCUUCGAGAGGAGGCAGAUUCCCCUCUACAUAGACGACACCCUGACGAUGGUGAUGGAAUUUCCUGAUAAUGUGUUAAAUCUCGAUGGACAUCAGAAUAAUGGUGCACAGCUAAAGCAGUUCAUUCAGCGACAUGGUAUGCUUAAGCAACAGGAUCUAAGUAUUGCCAUGGUGGUGACAUCACGCGAAGUCCUGAGUGCACUUUCUCAGCUUGUCCCAUGUGUUGGUUGUCGUCGCAGUGUGGAGCGUCUCUUUUCCCAGCUUGUAGAGUCUGGAAAUCCUGCUCUUGAACCCCUAACAGUAGGGCCCAAGGGAGUCCUGUCUGUAACUAGAAGCUGCAUGACUGAUGCAAAGAAGCUUUAUACAUUAUUUUAUGUACAUGGGUCCAAACUAAAUGACAUGAUAGAUGCUAUUCCAAAAAGUAAGAAGAAUAAGAGAUGUCAGUUGCACUCCUUAGAUACGCACAAGCCAAAACCUUUGGGAGGUUGUUGGAUGGAUGUAUGGGAACUAAUGUCGCAGGAAUGCAGGGAUGAAGUAGUUUUAAUUGACUCGAGUUGUCUUUUAGAAACACUAGAAACAUAUCUGCGAAAACACAGGUUUUGCACUGAUUGCAAAAAUAAAGUCCUCCGAGCAUACAAUAUCCUUAUUGGUGAACUUGACUGCAGCAAAGAAAAGGGCUACUGUGCUGCACUUUAUGAAGGCUUGCGGUGCUGUCCACAUGAACGACACAUACAUGUUUGCUGUGAAACAGACUUCAUUGCACAUCUUUUGGGUCGUGCUGAGCCAGAGUUCGCAGGAGGGUAUGAGCGAAGAGAAAGGCAUGCAAAGACAAUAGAUAUAGCUCAAGAAGAAGUUCUGACCUGCUUGGGAAUUCAUCUUUAUGAAAGACUGCAUCGAAUCUGGCAGAAGCUACGGGCAGAAGAGCAGACAUGGCAGAUGCUUUUCUAUCUUGGUGUUGAUGCUUUACGCAAGAGUUUUGAGAUGACCGUGGAAAAAGUACAGGGUAUUAGCAGAUUGGAACAACUUUGUGAGGAAUUUUCAGAAGAGGAACGAGUAAGAGAACUCAAGCAAGAAAAGAAACGCCAAAAACGGAAGAAUAGACGAAAAAAUAAGUGUGUGUGUGAUAUUCCUACUCCCUUACAAACAGCAGAUGAAAAGGAAGUAAGCCAAGAGAAGGAAACAGACUUCAUAGAAAAUAGCAGCUGCAAAGCCUGUGGCAGCACUGAAGAUGGUAAUACUUGUGUAGAAGUAAUUGUUACCAAUGAAAAUACAUCAUGUACCUGUCCUAGCAGUGGCAAUCUUUUGGGGUCCCCUAAAAUAAAGAAAGGCUUAUCUCCACACUGUAAUGGUAGUGAUUGUGGAUAUUCAUCUAGCAUGGAAGGGAGUGAAACAGGUUCUCGGGAGGGUUCGGAUGUUGCCUGCACUGAAGGCAUUUGUAAUCAUGAUGAACACGGUGAUGACUCUUGUGUUCAUCACUGUGAAGACAAAGAGGAUGAUGGUGAUAGUUGUGUUGAAUGUUGGGCAAAUUCUGAAGAGAACGACACAAAAGGAAAAAAUAAAAAGAAGAAGAAGAAAAGCAAGAUACUGAAAUGUGAUGAACAUAUCCAGAAGCUUGGAAGCUGUAUUACAGAUCCAGGUAAUCGAGAGACCUCAGGAAAUACCAUGCACACAGUGUUUCACCGUGACAAGACCAAAGAUACACAUCCUGAAAGCUGUUGCAGCUCUGAAAAGGGUGGGCAGCCAUUGCCUUGGUUUGAGCAUAGGAAAAAUGUACCACAGUUUGCAGAACCUACAGAAACGUUGUUUGGUCCCGAUUCCGGAAAAGGUGCCAAGAGCUUAGUUGAACUCCUUGAUGAGUCUGAAUGUACUUCAGAUGAGGAAAUCUUUAUCUCACAAGAUGAAAUACAGUCAUUUAUGGCUAAUAACCAGUCUUUCUACAGCAAUAGAGAACAAUACCGACAGCAUCUGAAGGAGAAAUUUAAUAAAUACUGCCGGUUAAAUGAUCACAAGAGGCCCAUUUGUAGUGGCUGGUUGACAACGGCUGGAGCAAAUUAAAUAAAUAAAAUAGCUCUGUCUUUCAAUGAAACACUCACGAUGACUACUGCGCCUUCUCUUUCGAAAAACUCUUAAUUUAGUGACUUAUGGCAAAAUUUUAUCUUAAAUCAAUGUGAUUCUUUCUUGUUUUGGGAGACGGUGGAGGUAUCCUCAUUAGUUCUUUCUUCAGGCUUGUGUCUUUAGUUGCGUGGCUGCGCAGGCCUGCCAUAUGAUUUAAGCCAUCUCUUUUCAUUAAAUGUUUCUCUUCCUGUGAGACUUACUAAAGCAACUUAGUGGCAAAAAGUAAUGUUGUACUUAUAAUUCUGUACAGAAAUGACAAUGAGCUGAAUAUAUGGUUUUACAAAGUAGACAUCCACUUGCAAAAUGUUUGGAUGUAAUGUUAAAGCGCAAUGUGCAAAAUUUAAAAUAAAGAAUAUUUAUUAAUACGCACAGUAAAA